ACUCCGGAUGGUUAGGACUGCCUGUCAGCACAGAGCUCCUCAAAUUUCACACAAGACAGGCUGUUCUCACAUUUCAAUGCACUCACCUGGAGGGCUUACCACAACAAAGAUGGCCGGACCCCUGCCCAGAGUUUCAGAUUCUUUGUUUUCUGCCAUGGAAUUGGCCAAAAUGUCAGACAUGACAAAGCUUCACCAAGCUGUGGCUGCAGGAGACUACAGCUUAGUGAAGAAGAUUUUGAAGAAAGGUCUCUGUGACCCAAACUACAAAGAUGUAGACUGGAAUGACCGGACCCCACUUCACUGGGCUGCAAUCAAAGGGCAAAUGGAGGUGAUACGGCUCCUGAUAGAAUAUGGAGCCAGGCCCUGCCUGGUUACUAGUGUGGGCUGGACCCCAGCUCAUUUUGCAGCAGAAGCAGGCCAUCUGAAUAUACUCAAAACUCUCCAUGCAUUGCACGCUGCCAUCGACGCCCCUGACUUCUUUGGAGACACACCGAAGAGGAUUGCACAGAUCUAUGGACAGAAAGCCUGUGUGGCAUUUCUGGAAAAGGGAAUAGAAUUUUGACUCUAUAUAAAUCAAGAAACGCCUGACUUCUUUAGUAGUUUGUAUUUGCAAGAUCUAAGAUCAUGGUAAACAUUAGGUCCUAAAAUCUUGGGGAAGGACAACAUGUCCUUCCUCUGACUUGUUAGCAAUCAAAUUGAGUAGGUUUUAAAUGUCUGUUAAUUGGAAGGGUUUGUUAUUUCAUUUUCAGCCAAAGGAGAGAGGUGCAUUUUAAGUAUCAGAAUUAGAUCAGCUUUGAGUUUGUACUAAAUUUGGAAUGUAAUAGAUUUUCAUAAAUUACGUGUGCCUUUUUGGAAAUGUCAACUGUCUUUAUGUCUGCUUGUAAAAGUUUCAAAAUAUGUUUUUCUCUCAAAAAGGCAACGUUAUUUCAUUUGCUUGAAUAUUAUGAUAGGAACGCUUACUGAUAUUACUUGAUAGUUUUAUAUAGCCUUGGAACUUUAACAUAUAAUAUAGCAGUAUUAAUCAUGAUAGUUGUACUUCUUUGAAACAUUAAAUUUGAGGAAACUAAUCUAUGUAAUUGUCUCCACUUCUUCACCUCUCACCCACGCUUCAGACUUCUUCCCUGAUCCCCAUACUGAAUCAGCUGUCACUCAAGUCAUUAGGGAGCUCCUCACGCUAAAUCAAUUGCCUCUUCUCAAUUCACAUCUUACCUCCACUUAAUUCGGUAUUUAAUAUUCCUGAAACUCUUCUCCCUUGUUUUAUCUGAUGCUAUUCUCUUUUAGUUUUUCUUCUACUUCUCUGAUAAUUCCUUAUGACUUUUAAAAUGUGCUUUUUCUAAGAAUAAAUCUUAUGAUAUGUUCUUGCGUGCCUUUUAAAUGCUGACAUUCCUUAGGGUCCUGCCCUUGGCUGUCCUCUACUGACUCUCUCUAAGUAAUCCCAGCCCCUCCCUAGUGACCAGGGAUCAACAUGAAAUAUGAUCCCAGCAUAACUGAAAUGCAGGAGGGGUGCUUGCCUCCAAAUAGUGGGGAGUGCUAUUACCAAGAAAAGUAGGCAGACAGUGUUGAGCCAGCAAAAACAAUAAAGGUCAGUCACAUCACGUGUGAGUCAUUUCUACUUAUUAUCAGCUCCCACUAAGAACUUCCCUGACAGAGCGUUUAGGGAGAAGAAUCCUGAAUUAAGGGGGGAUUAACCUGGAUCUUGAAAGCUAGCUGGCUAAUGAAGGAGGGAGAAAAACUGUUGAUUUAGAGUGAAGGCACCAACUUGGAAAUGUGCAUAGGUUGUGUGUAUAUGUGAGAAGGUGAGGGAUAGUGGAGUGCAGGGAUGAGUGGCCUGGCUAGGCAGAGCAUUCACACUAGAGAGGAAUGGAGCAUAAGGUCAGGUGACGGGGUGGGUGACCACAGUGAACUAGGCAAGCAGAAGAGUGUGAGCUCAUCAGGGGAGUCACAAGCUGAAACAGAUGCAUUAGCAAUUUAUUUGUGUAGUAGAGGAGUUGGCAGUGGUACUGCGUGGGAUUGAAGACUGCUAGACUUUAGGCAAGGGGAUCACUUAAGGAAUUUCUUAUUGAUUCACAUUUUGAGUAAGUUGGCUCCUGGGCUAGGUGAUGAAGAUAAAGGAUAUAAGAGAACUUCAAAAGAAGCCUAGACCAUAUGUGAUCAUUUUCUGAAUAUCCUAGGGAAUGUUGUGAAACAAUUCAGCUUUUGAUUCAGCCCCCCAAGUGAUAAACCUCUCAUUUAGCAAAUAUUUUUGAGUUCUACUAUGUGUAUGUCAUUGAGUUAGACACUAAAAACAACCUAAAAUAAACCAGAUACAGUGCUGGACAUCAAGAAGGUUAACUGUGUGGGAGACGAAAUAACUUGUUUACAUAAAUAACACUAAUACAAGACAGAGAGUGACUAGGCAGAGGAAAGACAUGGUGUGGUCUGAAGAUUGAAAGGUCACUUCCAGCUUAGGGUGAGGGACUAGUGAGUUUGCUGUCCUUUGAAUGAACUGUGCUUUUAAUAAUGGUUUGCACUUAAAAUGCUAUUUGCCUUCCCUAUACCAUUAUCUAUCCUCUUAAAUUCCAUUUGUCCUCAUAUUGGUUCAAAAGUGACUUUUCCAAGUACCUUUAAGCAAGUCACAUACUCACCAUUGGCCUCAUACAAAACUGUAUAUGUGUGUAUUUCCCAUUGUCUAUGUGUGUAUAAUGCUCUAUUUAUUUAUCCAUCCAUGUAUCCAUUUACAAUUAUAUGUAUUUUUACAGAAUCCAUACAUACGUAUAAUACAUAUGUGAUUGUGAGUGAUUCUCAUUUUGUUCCUUAUAUGUUUCUGUACUUUUAAAUUUUAUACAAGGAACACACAUCACUUUUAUGAUUAUGAAAAAUAAAACUAAAAAUAAACGAAAACAGUCUCGCAAUAAUCUGCAGGUUGCUCUAUAAAUGUGAGCACUUCAAGAAUCAGGAGCAUUUUCUUCAAGCUGAGUGACUAUCUUUGAGUCUGUUAACAUCUCACUCGGGUCCCACAAUUUUUCUCCACCUCCAAGUAGUUUCUUUAGUGUCUGAGACCUUCCCUAAGUGUAUGCUUGGAAAUGCUCAAACUUGGCCUCCUUCCUUCUCAACUGAACUGCGGUGUGCAGAACCUGUGAAUAAAGGCCGAUUCCCAGGCUGGAACAGGUCCUCCUGAUCCAAGUUCAGAAGGCUCUCUCUUC